GGCUGAGACUAUAGGUGCUUGCCACUAUGCCCAACUAAUAUUUGGAAUUUUCCUAUACAUGGAUUCCAGAGGGGUGACAGCAAAACGUGGGACCAUCCAGUUGCAGGAAAACAAGCUUAACACGCCCACUGAUUCUACAUUAUGCCUCUCCAGGCCCAGAACUUUCUCCAGUCAGCCUCCGCAGACCAAGCUCAUGACUCACAAUGGCCUAUUUAGGCCCAUACCCUACCUCACGGCAGUCUCCGCAGAUGAGGCUACUGCCUCACAACAGCCUCCACAGGCACAGCUCCACCGUUACAAUGGCCUCUUUAGACCCAGCUCCUGCCUCCCAGCCUUCUCUCCAGGCCCUGAACUUCCUCAAGUCGACCUCACCAGGCCCAGCUCAUGCUUCUUGGCAGCCUCUCCAGGCCCAGCUCCUGCAUCUUGGCAGCCUCUCCAGGCCCAGCCUCUGCCUCCCGUCAGCCUCUACAGUCCCAACAUCUGCCUCACAGCAGAUUCUUCAGGCCCAGCAUCUGCCUCACUGUGGACCACCCAAGCCAAGCUCCCAACCUUUCAGCAGCUUCUACACACCCAGCUCCUGCCACCCAGUGGCCUCUUUAGGCCAAGCUCAUGCCUCACAAGGGCCUUUCCAGGCCCAACUUUUGUCUCAUGGCAACCUUCCCUGGCCAGAUUCCUGCCUGUCUCCCAGCAGCCUAGACAGGCCCAGGUCUUGCCUCACACUGGCCUGUCUACAUCCAGCUCUUGCCUCACGGUGGCCUCUCCAGGCCCAGCUCCUGUCCCAGGACGUCAUCUCCAGGCCCAAAACUUCCUCAAGUCAGCCUCUCUAGUCCCAACUGCUGCCUCCUGGUGGCCUAUGAAGGCCCAAAAUCUCCUCAAGUUGACCUCUCCAGGCCCAGCUCCUGCCUCCUGUCAGCAUCUACAGGCCCAACCUCUGCCUCAUGGGGGCUUCUCCAGGCCCAGCUCUUCCUCUGGGCUGAGUCUACAGGCACAACUGCUGCUUCACAACAGCCUUUUUUGGCCCAGUUCCUGUCCAGCUCACAGCGGCCAAUGUAGGCCCAAAACUUCCUCAAGUCAAACUCCCCAGGCCCGCCUUCUGCUUCCCGGUGGCAUGAACAGGCCCAGCUUUGACUUGAGAACAGCCUCUGCAGGCCGUGCUCUUGCCUCCCAGGGGCUUCUCCAGGCCCAGCUCUUGCCUCAUGGCGGCUGCCCCAGGCCAAGUUUCUGCCUGCCUGCCAGCAGCCUCAACAGGCACAGCUCCUCCCUCACAGUGGCCCAUUUAGGCCCAACUCAUGACUGUCGGGCCAUUUCCAGGCCUAGUGCCUGCCUCCUGGCUGACUCUUGAAGCCCAAAACUUCCUCAAAUCAGCCUUUUGCCCAACUUCUGUCUACUGUCGGACUCUACAGGCCAGCCUCUGCCUCACAGUGGACCCUCCAGACCCAGAUGGUGUCUCACUGUGGCAUCCUCAGGCGAAGCUCCUGCCUUUUGGCAGCCUCUACGGGCCCAGCUCCUGCCUUGCAAUGGCCUCUUUAGGCCAAGCUCAUGCCCCACGGUGACUUUUCCAGGCACAGCUUUUGCCUUUUGCAGCCUGUCCAGGCCCAGAAUGUCCUUAACUCGGCAUCUCCAGGACGAGCUCAUCCUCCCAGUGCGUCUACAGGCCCGUCUCCUGCCUCACAACAACCUCCUUUGGCCCAACUCCUGCUGAGCUGCUUGGCAGCCUCUGUAGGCCACAGAGUUCUUAAAGUAAAGCUUUCCAGGCCCACCUUCGGCCUCCCAGCAGCCUCAGCAAUCAAACUAUUCCCUUACUGCGGCCACCGAAAGCCAAGUUUCUCCCUGCCUCACGGCAUCCUCCGAAAACUGAGCAUUUGCCUCACGGUGGCCUCCCCAGGCCACGAAUCUGCCUGCCUCCCAGGCAGCUGCUGUCUCACAAUGGUCUCUUUAGGCCCAGCUCAUGCUAAAAGACAGACUCUCCAGGCACAGCUCUUGCCUCCUGGCAGCCUCUGCAGGCCCAAAUUCUCCAAAAGUUGGCCUCUCCUAACUCAGCUUCUGCCUCAUGUCGGCCUACACAGGCCCAGACUCUUACCACACAGUAGACCCUCCAGGCCCACCACUUGCCUGAGCAUAGCCUCCUAAGGCCAAGCUCCUGCCUUUUGGCAGCUUCUACAGGCCCAGCUUCUGCCUCGCAAUUGCCUUUGUAGGCCAAGAUCAUGCCGCGAAGUGGCCUUUCCUAGCCUAACUUUUGCUUUUUGACGCAUACUCCUGUCCCAAAACUUCCUCCAGUCAGCCGGUCCAGGCCAAGCUCUUCCUCCCAAAGGCUUCUGCAGGCCAAAAUCGUCCUGAAGUCACCCUCUGCAGGCCCAGCUCCUGCCUCCAAGUGCUGUGUAGGCCAAGCUAAUGCCUCACAGCACACUUUCCAGGCUGAGCGUUUCCUUUUGUGCAUCCUCUCCAAGCCCUGAACUUACUCCAGUUGGCCUCUCCAGACCAAGCUCUCCCUCCCAGUGGCCUCUACAGGCCAAAACUGUCCUCAAGUCAGCCUCUCCAGGGCCAACUCCUAGCUACCGGUGGCUUCUGUAGGCCAAAAUCGACCUCAAGUCAGCCUCUUCACACCCAGCUCUUGUCUCUAAGUGGCCUUUCCAGGAGCAAAACUUCCUCAAGUCGGCCUCUCCAGGCCCAGCCUCCUGCUUCCCGAGGGCAUGUACAGGCCCAGCCUCUGCCUCACAGCAGACUCUCCACGCCCAGCUCUUCCCUGUCUGCUGCCUCUCCAGUCCAAAGCUGCUCCUGCCUUUCGGCAACUUGUACAGGCCCAACUCCUCCCUCACGGUGGCCUCUUUUCGCCCAACUCAUGCCUCUUGCAACCUGCCCAAGUGUCAGCUCCUGCCUCACACUGGCCUGUUGAGGCCCAGCUCAUGCCUCUCGUGGCCUCAACGGGCCCAGCCCCUGCCUGUCGGCGGCCUCUACAGGCCCGGCCUCUACCUCACAGUGGGCUC